AGUUUGUGUUUCAGACUUCCAUAUUUCCAUUUGCAGUUGGGUGAAGUGGUUAGAGCUGAAAGGGGACAGCUGGAGUCAAACAACUUAACUCAAAUAUCUGGGAACGAUUUCGCGCUGAGGAAGACCCUUUGGGACUUGUAGCUCCACUCCGGGGAACGGACUCGCCGGGACUGACAGUUGCCGGAAGUGAGGCUGCGGGGAAUGGCCGCCGCUGCGACCAUGGCGGCUGCGGCCCGGGAACUGGUGUUGCGGGCUGGGACCUCAGAUAUGGAGGAGGAAGAGGGCCCGCUGGUGAGAGCGCGGAGCUGUUUCUCCUCCGUAGUUCCGGUGCUCCUAGCUUCAGAAAGACCUGAGCUGGGUUUAGGCACAAGGGUGGGAACUUGGCUGCUACCCGUGAUAUUACCUGUUUGGCUCCCCGUACCCUUCCCUGUGAUCAGACCCGACCCUGAGCGGGACCCUAGUGGCUGAAACUCAUGUUCUGGGGCACAAAAUUUCAACUUCACUCCACAUUUUGGGGUAGAGUCACGAAGUAGUAUAGUGUAAAGGUUAAGAACAUGGCCUCUGAAGCCAGACUGCCUGAGUUCUAUCUCUGCCACUUACACGCUGUGUGCCCUUGGGCAAGUUAACCAGCUUCUCUGUGCCAUCAUUUCUCACACCUUUAAGGUGAGGAAGAUAGAACCUAUUGUAUACAUCGUCGUUAGGAUUAGAUGAAUAUGUGUAAGAUUGCACCUGGCAUGCAGGCGGGUGGUCCUGGGCUCCAGGAACCACUGCAACUUGGGGAGUUGGAUAUCACUUCUGAUGAAUUCAUCCUGGAUGAAGUGGAUGGGUGUAGAUCUCCGUCACUAUUCAAAGCAAGUUGAGCUGGAGCUACAGCAGAUUGAACAGAAAUCCAUUCGGGAUUAUAUUCAAGAGAGUGAGAAUAUAGCAUCUCUACACAACCAGAUCACAGCCUGUGAUGCUGUCCUGGAGCGAAUGGAGCAGAUGUUGGGAGCUUUUCAGAGUGACCUCAGCUCCAUCAGCUCUGAGAUCCGGACACUGCAGGAACAGUCAGGAGCCAUGAACAUUCGACUUCGAAAUCGCCAGGCAGUUCGGGGGAAACUUGGGGAGCUUGUUGAUGGUCUGGUGGUGCCUUCUGCUCUGGUCACGGCAAUUCUGGAGGCUCCAGUGACAGAGCCCAGGUUCUUGGAGCAGCUACAGGAGCUGGAUGCCAAGGCAGCCGCAGUCAGAGAGCAGGAAGCUAGAGGCACAGCAGCCUGCGCAGAUGUCAGAGGCGUGCUCGAUCGGCUCCGGGUCAAGGCAGUGACGAAGAUCCGAGAGUUUAUCCUCCAGAAGAUUUAUUCCUUCAGGAAACCCAUGACCAACUAUCAGAUCCCCCAGACGGCCCUGCUGAAGUACAGGUUCUUCUAUCAGUUUCUGCUGGGCAAUGAACGAGCAACAGCAAAGGAGAUCAGGGAUGAAUAUGUGGAGACGCUGAGCAAGAUUUACCUGUCUUACUACCGCUCUUACCUGGGGCGGCUCAUGAAGGUGCAGUAUGAGGAAGUCGCUGAGAAAGAUGAUCUAAUGGGUGUGGAAGAUACAGCAAAGAAAGGAUUCUUCUCAAAGCCAUCGCUCCGCAGCAGGAACACCAUUUUCACCCUAGGAACCCGCGGCUCUGUCAUCUCCCCCACUGAACUUGAGGCCCCCAUCCUGGUGCCUCACACAGCGCAGCGCGGAGAGCAGAGGUAUCCAUUUGAGGCCCUCUUCCGCAGCCAGCACUACGCCCUCCUAGACAAUUCCUGCCGCGAAUACCUUUUCAUCUGUGAAUUUUUUGUUGUGUCUGGCCCAGCUGCACACGACCUGUUCCAUGCUGUCAUGGGCCGUACACUCAGCAUGACCCUGAAACACCUGGAUUCUUAUCUAGCUGACUGCUACGAUGCCAUUGCUGUUUUUCUCUGUAUCCACAUUGUUCUCCGGUUCCGUAACAUUGCAGCAAAGAGGGAUGUUCCUGCCCUGGACAGGUACUGGGAACAGGUGCUUGCCUUGCUAUGGCCACGGUUUGAACUGAUCCUGGAGAUGAAUGUUCAGAGCGUCCGAAGCACUGACCCCCAGCGCCUAGGGGGGUUGGAUACUCGGCCCCACUAUAUCACACGCCGCUAUGCAGAGUUCUCCUCCGCUCUUGUCAGUAUCAACCAGACAAUUCCUAAUGAACGGACCAUGCAAUUGCUGGGACAGCUGCAGGUGGAGGUGGAGAAUUUUGUCCUCCGAGUGGCAGCUGAGUUCUCCUCAAGGAAGGAGCAGCUUGUGUUUCUGAUCAACAACUAUGACAUGAUGCUGGGUGUGCUGAUGGAGCGGGCUGCAGAUGACAGCAAAGAGGUUGAGAGCUUCCAGCAGCUGCUCAAUGCUCGGACACAGGAAUUCAUUGAAGAGUUGCUGUCUCCCCCUUUUGGGGGUUUAGUGGCAUUUGUGAAGGAGGCUGAGGCUUUGAUUGAGCGUGGACAGGCUGAGCGACUUCGAGGGGAAGAAGCCCGGGUAACUCAGCUGAUCCGUGGCUUUGGUAGUUCCUGGAAAUCAUCAGUGGAAUCUCUGAGUCAGGAUGUAAUGCGGAGUUUCACCAACUUCAGAAAUGGCACCAGUAUCAUUCAGGGAGCGCUGACCCAGCUGAUCCAGCUCUAUCAUCGCUUCCACCGGGUGCUGUCCCAGCCGCAGCUCCGAGCCCUCCCUGCCCGGGCUGAGCUCAUCAACAUUCACCACCUUAUGGUGGAGCUCAAGAAGCAUAAGCCCAACUUCUGAUGUGCCAGAAACCGCCCUGAGAUCUGCCGGUCAUCUCCAUGGACUUCUGCACCCCAUUCCAUACCCUUCUUCACCUGGGGUACCCCUUCCAGUUUUCCCCUUGCUUCCCAGGCCCUUGACAUGGCUUACCUGCCUUCACUCCCAGCACCUUGCCCAACAGGAUAAGCUGGAUCCCCUUGGCCUUCUGAAUAUCCCAGUGUCUUCAGGUUUCCCAAGACCACUUCCCUGUGGGCUUCCAAAAUGGCCUUUAUCAUUUCUCCAGUCUGUCACCCUCCUUUCCUGCUCCCAUACACCCAAGGCUUGUUUCUUCCCCUGUAAAAACCACUGCCUCAAUCUCUGGUUCACUCAACUAGUCACCAUGUCCUGAGGCAUGAAGCCUCCUCAGCUCUUGGAAUUGCUGGCAAGGGGUGACUGCCUCUGAGUCAUUGUGUUUUUCAAAGUGAUUUCUUUUCUGUAGCUUUUUGACCUAAGAUCUCAGCAAUUUGAACACUAACCUCUCCCCUCCUGGCUCAAGAAUUACUCCGAAGUCAGUCUGCAGAAAAUAAAUAUUUAGUAUGACAUGA